AGAGGCGGAAGUAAAAGCGAACUACAGUGGAUGGGUGCAGUUCAGGGUGAGAUUGGGAAGGUGAGAUAGCUGUUCUCCAGCCUUUCUGGAGGGAUGCAGAGCCUUUCCUUAGGACAAACAAGAAAGUACUGAUCUGAUUUCCAGCUGACGCAUUCUGCCCCUUUAUUCCAGUAGAGGUCAGUCGAGCAUCUGGAAGAGAAAACAGGCUGUUGAACUAUGCAAGCAUUUCAAAAGGUUUGAACUACCUAACCAUUAUGGCACCAGGAAACCUCUGGCAUAUGAGAAAUAACUUUCUCUUUGGUUCAAGAUGUUGGAUGACUCGAUUUUCAGCAGAAAACAUCUUCAAAUCAGUUUCAUUUAGGCUUUUUGGUGUGAAGUGUCAUAAUACAGACAGUGAGCCUUUGAAAAAUGAGGACCUACUGAAAAACUUACUUACUAUGGGAGUAGAUAUUGACAUGGCAAGGAAACGACAGCCUGGAGUUUUUCAUAGGAUGAUUACCAAUGAGCAGGACCUGAAGAUGUUCCUUCUUUCCAAAGGAGCUAGCAAAGAAGUGAUCGCUAGCAUCAUAUCAAGAUAUCCACGAGCAAUAACACGUACUCCCGAGAAUCUUUCAAAACGGUGGGAUCUGUGGAGAAAGAUUGUGACAUCAGACCUUGAAAUUGUAAAUAUUUUGGAACGUUCUCCUGAAUCCUUUUUUCGGUCCAAUAACAACCUAAACUUAGAGAAUAAUAUAAAGUUCCUCUACUCAGUUGGAUUGACCCGUAAAUGCCUUUGUCGAUUGUUGACCAAUGCCCCUCGUACCUUCUCCAAUAGUCUUGAUCUGAAUAAACAGAUGGUUGAAUUUUUGCAGGCAGCCGGUUUGUCAUUGGGUCACAAUGAUCCCGCAGAUUUUGUCAGAAAGAUAAUUUUUAAAAACCCUUUUAUCUUAAUUCAGAGCACCAAGCGGGUGAAAGCUAACAUUGAAUUCUUACGGUCAACUUUCAAUUUGAACAGUGAGGAACUGCUGGUUCUGAUAUGUGGUCCAGGAGCUGAAAUCCUAGACCUUUCCAAUGACUAUGCCAGAAGAAGCUACGCAAACAUCAAAGAGAAGCUGUUUUCUCUUGGAUGUACUGAAGAAGAGGUACAGAAGUUUGUCUUAAGCUAUCCAGAUGUGAUCUUCUUGGCAGAGAAAAAGUUUAAUGAUAAAAUAGACUGCCUCAUGGAAGAAAACAUUAGCAUUUCACAAAUAAUCGAAAAUCCUCGGGUUCUGGAUUCAAGCAUAAGUACUUUAAAAAGUCGAAUCAAAGAAUUGGUAAAUGCUGGCUGUAACUUGAGUACUUUAAACAUCACUCUUCUAUCUUGGAGUAAAAAAAGAUAUGAAGCUAAAUUGAAAAAGUUAAGCAGAUUUGCCUAAGGAUGCCAAUGUUUUUAAUUCUCAGGAACUGUGAAUAUGUUAUGCCACAUUGCAAAAGAAUUUUGCAGAAGUGAUUAAUUUAAAAUGUUAUUAAGGGCCUUGAGAUGGGGAGAUUAUCCUGAAUUACUUUGGAGGGCCUAAUAUAAUUGUAGGGAUCUUUAAAAGUUGAAGAGGGAGGCAAAAGAGGAGGUCAGAGUGAUCCUGUAUAAGAAAGACAACUACUUUUGAAGGAAGUUAAAAGGUGGCUUUGAAGGAGGAAGACACCUUGAGCCAAGGAAUGAAGGGGGCCUGUAAAAAAAGAUUGAAAAGGCAAGGAAACAGAUUCUCCAUUAGAGUCCCCAGAAAGGAAUGCAGCCUUGCUGGCACCUUUUUAGCCCAGUGAGAUCAAUGUCAAACUUCUGACCCACAGAACCAUAAGAUGGUAAAUUUGUGUUGUUUUAAACCACUGAGUCAGUGAUAAUUUGCUGAAGAAGCAAAUAGAUUAACAUAGCAACUAAGUAGAUGAUUAGUUGCAUUAUAGGUGAAGUCAAAAAUACAGUCCUUUAGUAAAGUCUCUAUUUCUUCCUUUUAUAAGAGUAAUUAUAUUUAAAAAAUCUACCUACCCUUCUGGAAUUGCUAAUGUUAGUGUUUAUAAAGUCUUAAAUGUGUGCAUAAAAAACUAAAUGUGAAUAUAAAAUCUAAAUAAAGGAAUAUGUUUGCCUAAUAUAGUUUAAGGAAAUGAUAAUCAUUUCUGUGCAUUUUGUUGGCAUUUCAGCUAAUAUUAAAGAGUAAUUUUCAGAGGCAUUGACUUAAAAAAUGGCAAAUCAGAUAAUGUCGGUAUUUUCAAGAUACAAUCUAGCUCUGACAUAAACUGAAAGACGUGAGACAAAUUAUAUGACCUUAAUUUUAAUUGUUUUCCAGAGGCAUUUGUUUUCUAGAUGUGGUUUUUGAAUUAAAUAACAUAAUGGUGCUCAACCUUUUAAACCUCAUUUGCUAUCAGUGAUACUUCAAAAAACCUUAUUCCUACUAUUGAUAAAAACAAUAUGUCUGCUUUUCUAAGGCCAUUUAUAUAUUCAACGAUACUCCUAUUAUAAUUUGGUUAACUAUUUGAUGGCAAGCAUGGCAUAGUUUAGAAAGCAAGAGCUUUAGAGUGAUGUAUCUGGGCACCAUUCCUGAGUAACUUGUGUUAAUGUUUUAAAUUUACUAAACCUGUUUUUCUCAUCUGUAACACCAGAAAUUGACCUUCCAGAGUUGGUAGGAAUCAAAUGAAAAAGCACCUCUAAGGUUUCUUGCACAUAGUAAUGAUGCAAUCAGUGAUAGCUAUAAUAAAAAGAUAGUAUUUUAAAAAGCAGCUUUAUACAUAAUUCACAUAUUCAAUUUACCUAUUUAAAGUCUAACACAGUUCAAUUUAUAUAUAGAGUUGUGCAACUUUAUCUUCCAUUGCUUAUAAUACAUUUAUAAUUUAUUGGAAAAUUUAUAAGGAAAAUGAAUUUCUUACAGUUAUGGAAGCUGAGAAAUCCUAGGUUGAGGGGCCACAUCUGGUGAGAGCCUUCUUGCUGGUGGGGACUCUGAAGAGUCCUGAGGCGGCACAGUGUAUCACAUGGCGAUUGCUAAUGUACUUAGGUCUCUUUUCCUCUUAUAAAGCCACCAGUCCACUCCCAUGAUAGCCUAUUAAUUCAUUAAUCCAUGAAUAGAUUAAUCAAUUUCUGAUGACAUAGCCCUUAUGAUCCAGUCACCUCUUAAAGGCCCCACCUCUCAAUACUGCCACAUUGGGGAUUAAAUUUCAACAUGAGUUUUGGAGGGGAUGGAUAGUCAAACCAUAGCAGCAACCAUCACCACAAUCUAGUUUUAGAAUAUGUUUGCAGUCCUAACAGAAACCUUGUACCUGUUAGUGAAUCCCCAUUAUUUCCCUCCAUUUGUUCCCCCAAGCCUAAGCAAAAAUGAAUCUGUUUUCUGUGUCUAUAAAUUUGUUUAUUCUGAGCAUUUCAUAUAAAUGGAAUCAUACAGUAUGGUCUUUUGUGACUGGCUUCUUUCACUUAGCAUAUUUUCAAGGUUCAUCCAUGUAGCACAUAUUAGUAUUUCAUUUUUUUUGGCAAGUAAUAUUCCAUUGUAUGGGUACAGUAGUAUUGGGAAUACAUUUUACUGUUAUGGCUUAAAGUAUUGAUUUCUUAAGUCUUCUGAAUUGUACGCGAGUGUUUUCUGAGGUAUUGUUUUGGAAUCUAACAAGCUCAUAAGGGACUUGAAGGAGGUGGGUAGAAGAGAUAAUAGUUUAUUGACAUCAGCAGAUCAUAGGAUUGUAGCUGGGCUGAUGAGAAAUGGUAUAGCAACGAUAGUUGCAAGUGGCCAGAGAGAAUGUGGGUUGCACUGAAGUACAGUACAGCACUUGAUCAUUGGGCAGUAGGGGAUGGGGGAAGGAAAACUUUGGAGAAACAAACAGAUAAUGCCUGUCAGGCAAAAUUAACAUGUCAUACUUUAAGGUUUGAGUCUGAUCAAGGGAGAGUCAAUUCUUUUUUUUUAAAGAUAGAAUUAUAGAAAUAUUGGCCAGCCAUGUAAUCCCAGCUCACGCCUGUAAUCCCAGCAAUUUGGGAGGCCGAGGUGGGAGGAUUGCUUGAGCCCAGGAGUUCAAGACCAGCCUGGGUAAUACUAGCAAGAUAUCAUUGCUAGUAGGGAAAAAAAAAAAAAAAAA